GAGGGCCCGUGUCCCCGCGGAGGUCAAGGCCGAGAGAGGGCCCGUGUCCCCGCGCAGGUCAAGGCCCAGAGUCCCCGUGCUCGCACAGAUGGUGUCCUGGGGCCCAGUCGCGCUCCCCGCUCGCGGCAGCCCCCGUGUACUGGGCCUUGCAAAGUCCGUUAGGAGCGCUCCAGGGCGACAGUGCCCAGCGGUUAACAAGUGGUGAAACAGGAAGCAACAUCCCAUCAGGAAGAACCUGAGGGUGCCAUCCAGUAGCUUCGCCUCACGUCACUGACUGCCCUCAGUCAGAAAUCUUGACUCGCAACUUUGGAGGGUGGGUCUCUGAAGGAAUUUCAGGUCUUACACAGAGAUGAGUUGUGCUGCUCUCUGAGGAGAACGAAGCUGGUUGGAACGUUGGAAGCUGCUCUCUGACUACACUUCACAAGCAAGGGGCACCUUUUGUGGACUGACAUUUCAGAAAGGGAUGUUGUGAAACAAAAGCUGACAUUUAUAUAUAUAUACAUAUAUACAGUAUUUGAGUUCCUCAGUAGAAAGCUAUCAUAUAUACUCAGAUGGCGUUAUUCCCUCUGGUCCCCACUGCUCUGGCCAAACCUUCUCUCUGCUGACUGCAUCUAUUGCUGUGAGCUGAUUGUCCUCUAGUUUCUCCAUCUCCUGAGGCAUGCUUCACACCACUGCCAGAAGAGCUGCCAGAAUGUUUUGGACGUUUAAAGAAUGGUUCUGGUUGGAAAGAUUCUGGCUUCCUCCAACAAUAAAGUGGUCAGAUCUUGAGGAUCACGAUGGACUCGUCUUUGUAAAACCUUCUCAUUUAUACGUGACAAUUCCAUAUGCUUUUCUCUUGCUGAUUAUCAGACGUGUAUUUGAAAAAUUUGUUGCUUCACCUCUAGCAAAAUCAUUUGGCAUUAAAGAGACAGUUCGAAAGGUUACACCAAAUACUGUCUUAGAGAAUUUUUUCAAACAUUCCACAAGGCAACCAUUGCAAACUGAUAUUUAUGGACUGGCAAAGAAGUGUAACUUGACGGAGCGCCAGGUGGAAAGAUGGUUUAGGAGUCGGCGGAAUCAAGAGAGGCCUUCCAGGCUGAAGAAAUUCCAGGAAGCUUGCUGGAGAUUUGCAUUUUACUUAAUGAUCACUGUUGCUGGAAUUGCGUUUCUUUAUGAUAAACCUUGGCUAUAUGACUUAUGGGAGGUUUGGAAUGGCUAUCCCAAACAGCCCCUGCUGCCAUCCCAGUACUGGUACUACAUUUUAGAAAUGAGUUUUUAUUGGUCUCUGUUAUUUAGACUUGGCUUUGAUGUCAAGAGAAAGGAUUUUCUAGCUCAUAUCAUCCACCACCUGGCUGCUAUUAGUCUGAUGAGCUUCUCUUGGUGUGCUAAUUAUAUUCGCAGUGGGACCCUCGUGAUGAUUGUACACGAUGUGGCUGACAUUUGGCUGGAGUCUGCUAAGAUGUUUUCUUAUGCUGGAUGGACGCAGACCUGUAACACCCUGUUUUUCAUCUUCUCCACCAUAUUUUUCAUCAGCCGCCUCAUUGUUUUUCCUUUCUGGAUUUUAUAUUGCACGCUGAUCUUGCCUAUGUAUCACCUCGAGCCUUUCUUUUCAUACAUCUUCCUCAACCUACAGCUCAUGAUCUUGCAGGUCCUUCACCUUUACUGGGGUUAUUACAUCUUGAAGAUGCUCAACAGAUGUAUAUUCAUGAAGAGCAUCCAGGAUGUGAGGAGUGAUGACGAGGAUUAUGAAGAGGAAGAGGAAGAGGAAGAAGAAGAGGCUACCAAAGGCAAAGAGAUGGAUUGUUUAAAGAACGGCCUCAGGGCUGAGAGGCACCUCAUUCCCAAUGGCCAGCAUGGCCAUUAGCUGGAAGCCUACAGGACUCCCAUGGCACAGCAUGCUGCAAGUACUGUUGGCAGCCUGGCUUCCAGGCCCCACACCGACCCCACAUUCUGCCCUUCCCUCUUUCUCACCACCGCCUUCCCUCCCACCUAAGAUGUGUUUACCAAAAUGUUGUUAACUUGUGUUAAAAUGUUAAAUAUAAGCAUGCCCAUGGAUUUUUACUGCAGUUAGGACUCAGACUGGUCAAAGAUUUCAAAGAUUUCUCCACAGAACCGUCUCAGUUCUAAUUGCACUCCCUCAUGCAUGUCACUUUCUCAGGGGCUCGCUUUGUUAUAGACCCUUUCGCCUCGCCACCUUGCCUGUCCUCAGGACGCUUUCACAGGUGCUAAGUGAUCUCAUUUUUCCCAGGUGUGUUUGGCCACAAAGAGCAGCUUCUUUCUCAAAAUGAGUUAGAAGUGGCAGUGGGACAGGAGCGGAAGGACCACACCAGGAGACACUUCCAUCCUGAAGCUUAGGUGCCUCAUCUCCACAGGGCGGUGGCAGUCCCUGCCUGCCACCCCACAGGGUUACAGCAAGGAUUAAGUGAGAUCACAGAAGUUUAAGUACACACUGUCAACCGUGGGGUCAUCGUGAACCAACCCACUUUGCACUGUUUGGGAGACAGAAACCUGGCUAAACAUGGCACUGCAAUGGGCCUGAACAAAAGGCAGAAUCUUUAAAAAUUCCUCUUAAAUGACUCUGGAGAUACCUGGAAAUGAAAGUGCCAAGAAAGGUGUUCCAUUUUAUUUGCUAACUAUUUAUGCAUUAGCUCCCCAAGGGUCAUUCUCAGAUUCUCCUGGAAUUCUUCUCCCUCAGGACCCAUGGUUCAAGGAAGGAAGCUUAGGCCCUGUUCCUUCCUGUCCUUUGCUGGUCUUUCCCUUUUUUCCUUUCUAGGAGGGAAGCUUCUGUGCUGCUGCCCUGAGCCCUUCCUUCAGGCCAGCACAGUACCUGGGGACCUCCACGGGGGAAUGGGAUCCAGGCCAGGUUGCUUGCUGAGCCUCAUCACCCAGGAGGCCUGAGCCUCUGGGGAGGGCACGCAUGUACACUGCCAGACCCAGGGGAGAUCUUGGGAACAGAGGAUGCUACGUGAUUUCCUCUGGCUUCCAACCCAAUCAGCCUGCAUCACAGUGAAACACAACACAAAAGGCCAUAAAAGGCAUACCCCUGAGAAAUGUUUAAGGGCAGGUGCUAGAGUCAGUGCCAGCUCCCUGGGAGGAGGGAUAGGGACGGGCAGAUCAGUAGCCAGCUUGUCCUCACCCUCCGGAAGGGAGCACCGGAGAAGACUUGCACACGUCCCUGCCUCCCUUGCGGCCUUGUCACCAGAGGGACACAUCUCCUGGGCACAAUGUGCAGGGCUGACCUGGGAGACUUCUCAGGUGGCUGCUGGCUGAGGAGAGGCCAGGCCUUCCCAAGGAAGACCCUGAGUAAAAUCUGCAUCUGUCCUCACCACCUGGCACAGUCUCUCAUAACGGUCAGAUUUUGUAUGUUCAUCCUAUUUAUUCAGGGGCUCGUACUAGAAAGCCACAGGAGAGGUCGGCUUGUAGGGACUGGAAAAUCAGCCCCAAGCAGAGCAGCUGCAGGGCCCCUGGAGCCGGAAGGACACUGCACAGAACAGACUGCGUUAUUGUUAUUUUUAAAUAAAAAUAUACAUUUGAAACCUUAAGGCUAAACAAAAAUAAACAAAAAAUCCUUUAGAAUUCUUUCCACAACAAUAUCUCUUUCUGAGAAAUUGUUACAAACAAGGUCAGAUUUUCUCUGUAUAACAUUUGCUUUUAUGAGGACAAUAUCAUAUGCAUUAUAUGCAUAAUAUGAUAUUAUAAAUCAAAAUGCCUGCACCCACUUUAGGGUAUAGCUAUUGACUUAUUAUUAAUAUUAUAUUAUUAUUAUUUUGCUGGAAGAAGGUCACACUAAGAUAUAAUUUUUUAUGUUUUCAGUUAACGGUAUGCUUUCUUCUUUGCUUAUUUGGUUUUUGUCUCUGUACCAAAUAUCUUCUUGCUUAAGGUAGAAAAGUAUUUGUUUACCUCUAUCUCCAGUUUUUUUUCUUAUUUGAAUGUUGAAGGUAAAAUUGAUAUACCAAUUUUAACUAUUUCUGAUACAGCUGAAAGCACUAAACUACUUCAUAAGAAGUAGAUACUCAUUUUUGUAACACUAUUUAGGGCUUUUGUGGUUAAUUUUAAAGGAAACCACUCUUUCUACAGGAAACAAGGGCUCAGGAUUCUUCAGAUGACCUUAUAAAAAUGCAGUCCACAGUGCUAUCAAUAUUGUAACAGUAAUGACUACAAUAAAGCCAAAAGUCCAGUGUA